GUCGUGUGUGUUUGGGGCCCGCGCGGGUUGCGCGCCCUCCGCCUUCGCGCCUCCUGCCCCCGAGGCCCUACUGCUGCCCCUGUGCCCCUCGCCCCGCCGGGCGUCGCGGGCCAACAUGGGCCAGGAAGAGGAGCUGCUGAGGAUCGCCAAAAAGCUGGAGAAGAUGGUGGCCAGGAAGAACACGACCACACAAUAGUCAGAGAAGCCUGGUCAGGACCCAGGCCCCAGUCCUCACCUUGUGGCCUCCCACAGGAAGGGGCCCUGGACCUUCUGAAGAAGCUGCACAGCUGCCAGAUGUCCAUCCAGCUACUACAGACAACCAGGAUUGGAGUUGCUGUUAAUGGGGUCCGCAAGCACUGCUCAGACAAGGAGGUGGUGUCCUUGGCCAAAGUCCUUAUCAAAAACUGGAAGCGGCUGCUAGACUCCCCUGGACCCCCAAAAGGAGAAAAAGGAGAGGAAAGAGAAAAGGCAAAGAAGAAGGAAAAAGGGCUUGAGUGUUCAGACUGGAAGCCAGAAGCAGGCCUUUCUCCACCAAGGAAAAAACGAGAAGACCCCAAAACCAGGAGAGACUCUGUGGACUCCAAGUCUUCUGCCUCCUCCUCUCCAAAAAGACCAUCGGUGGAAAGAUCAAACAGCAGCAAAUCAAAAGCGGAGAGCCCCAAAACACCUAGCAGCCCCUUGACCCCCACGUUUGCCUCUUCCAUGUGUCUCCUGGCCCCCUGCUAUCUCACAGGGGACUCUGUCCGGGACAAGUGUGUGGAGAUGCUGUCAGCAGCCCUGAAGGCGGACGAUGAUUACAAGGACUAUGGAGUCAACUGUGACAAGAUGGCAUCAGAAAUCGAAGAUCAUAUCUACCAAGAGCUCAAGAGCACGGACAUGAAGUACCGGAACCGCGUGCGCAGCCGCAUAAGCAACCUCAAGGACCCCAGGAACCCCGGCCUGCGGCGGAACGUGCUCAGUGGGGCCAUCUCCGCAGGGCUUAUAGCCAAGAUGACGGCAGAGGAAAUGGCCAGUGAUGAACUGAGGGAGUUGAGGAAUGCCAUGACCCAGGAGGCCAUCCGUGAGCACCAGAUGGCCAAGACUGGCGGCACCACCACUGACCUCUUCCAGUGCAGCAAAUGCAAGAAGAAGAACUGCACCUAUAACCAGGUGCAGACACGCAGUGCUGAUGAGCCCAUGACUACCUUUGUCUUAUGCAAUGAAUGUGGCAAUCGCUGGAAGGAUGAGCAAGUCUGUCAUUUGAGCACAGAUGGAAUCGGCUUCCUGAGAUCCACAGAGGAGAGGAAAAACAUUCUGCACUUGGACCACGCCUCUUUGGAAAGUGCUUCCACAGAUGGUAUUUCCUUUGAACCUGGCCACAGCCAAGGAUGGGAAACAGGAAGGCUGAGCCCUGUCAGAAAGGAGUUGAACCUAAAUGCCACCAGGCCAUCCUUCCCUCCUAAGGAAGCUCUGAAAGUCUUACCCAAGUCUGUAACUCAGACUGCCCCAGCUCCUGCAAAGGCAGAAGUUUUGUUUUCACGCAUGGGAGCCAAACAAAGACUCCUCCCAGAGUGCUCCUUCCUGCCAAGUCUCCUGAAGGAACAGAGUGUGGUCACGUGCCUAUUGUCAGUUUCCAACUGCUCUCUGACUUGCAUGUGCACCAUGUGAUGUCUGGGCCACCAGGCAGGCUGCAGGUGCUCCAAAAGUUCUAAGGUACUUAGCAAGAAGUACAAGAUAAGUCAGGAUCCCUGGUUUCAGGUCCCAUUCUGCCCUACUCAUGCUGAGCAUGUUACUCACCUCAUUGAGCAAAAGAGUAAUAAUAAUGCCUUUCUCCCAGGUUUGAUGAUGUGAGGAUCAUUUUGAUAUGAGGGUUAUCAUGUAUGCAUAAACACUUUGCAAACAACUACAA